AUAAAUUCAUUUAACAAAUGUCUACUGAGUAAUUACUGUGUGCCUGGCACUCUUCUAAAUGUUGGAAGUAUGACAGCAGUGGACUUAAUAGAAAAUCCCUGCCCUGGUAAGAUAGCAUUUUCUUGUAGGUUAUAUUUGCAGUGAUUGACAUCACCUUGACCUUUAGCUGCCUCAGGCUGAGUACAGGGAUGCAACCUAGACCUCUUACCUAGCCAGUUUCUGCUAGAGGUUACAAGUCAAGUUGUGCCAGGGAACUUCAUAUGUCCCCUCUAUGAGUCAGUCUUUAUAGAUCUUGGGAAUCUCUGGAGGAUUCUAAGCAUCAGAGUGAAAUUUCGGUUCACCUAAAAAAUGUAGCAUCUAUGCAAUAAGUGUACUAAUUUGACACCAGAGGGACUGUUUUUCUCUUUUAGUAAUUUUGAAUGUUGUAGUCUAAGUUGAAUAGAAGAGAAAAUUACUAUAAUCAUAUAUCAACAUUUUAAAGUAGAUUUUUCAUGUAGAUGAAGGAAAGAACCUUAGAGAUUCUGCCCUUUAAAUUUUUUUAAUGUUUUAUUUUUGUUUUCAAGUACAGAAUGGCCUCUUGUAAAUUGGUGCCUGUGUUAUUGAUUUAUUUUUAUUUUUAUUUAUUUAUUUUUGAGAUGGAGUCUUGCUCUGUCGCCCAGGCUGGAGUACAGUGGCGCAAUCUCGGCUCACUGCAACCUCCGCCUCCUGGGUUCAAGCAAUUCUCCUGCCUCAGCCUCCCAAGUAACUGAGAUUACAGGUGUGAUGCCUGUGUUAUUUUUAAAUGAGGCAACUGAGGACUUUGCCCAAAGUCUCAAUGCUAGCUGAUGGUAGAGCCUAGCCUUCUGUUGCUUGGCCGUGUAUUCUUCUUUCCUUUAGAAAUAGAAAUGUCCACCACUUAGUACAGUAAUCCAUUGGUACGGUGUCAAACUAAAAAUUGGCUGUUUUAUGAGUUUGUUUCUUGAACGUAUUUUGAAAUCUCUCUCUCUCCUGAAUCCUCAUAGUGCUAUAUAUUACCUCCCCAUGGCAUUUAUUACUUUCCACUCAUAUUGUAAUUAUCUUCUAUUAACAAGAUUUUUUUUAGAUGAACUGUCUUUGAGAAUAGAGUCUGUGUAUGUUUCUUCUUUGUGUAUUCCCCACAGCUCUUAACAGAAUGCCUGGCAUUCACUAGGUACUCAAAUUAUUAAACAUGUUCUCAUAGAGAUUAUAUUUUGGGUUUGGUAACAAUGUGAAACCACAGGAAUCUAUUUAGUCUACAACAUUUUAAGAGGCUGUUUGGCUUACCAUCAGAUCUAGGUUUGAAUUCUGGCUCCAUCCUCAUCUUGGCUGUGUGAUCUUGAAUAGGUCACUUAACAUCAUUUUCCUCAUCUGUGAAAUGAGAAUAUGUGCCCCAUCUAGCUUUAAGAUUUAGGUAAAAUGUAUACAAAGGGUCUAGUGCCUGAUGUACUAAUAGCUACUCAAUGAAUGGUAACUAUUAUUGUUAGAAAUUUAUUUUCUAUUUAUUAUAAGUGCAUUUUAAAAUAACAUUAAAUAGCUCUAUUACCUAUGUGAAGGAUGUACAGUAAGAAAAAGGUCCAUGGUGAAAAGCUGACAGCAUUUUGGUAUGGUCAGCAGAUUGCCCAGUCUGGGCUUUUUAGCUUACCAAUUGCUUAUUUAAGAUGUUUGAUUUGGGGCUCUUAAGAACUGGUUUACCAUACUAAAACUCAAAGAGACUGAUGUAUAAACUAGAAUGGAAGUUUAUUAAUAAGUCAUUAAAAAUGUAUUCUCACAUAGGAAAACAAAUGCCACAGUGGAAUCCAGAUUGUAAUCAGAAGCUUGCUUGAGGAAAAGGAUAGUGGAUUGGGUAUCUGGUACUGCAUUAAUCUCCUGCAUCAAUCGUGACCUACCACUUAGCUGCGUCAGGACCCCUUCUCUUCUAGAGAGUGCUAAAGGCACUGCCUAAUCACCUCUCAUAAAUCCCCUGUUCUAACUUACAUAGUUGUCUGCUUUCGGGUUGCAUGUUCUUAAAAGCAGACAGCAAAACCCUGGAGGAGGUUUUAUACUUAGUCAUUAGCCUGUCAUUCCUGCUGGAGUUUUACAGCCUCACCUUAGUUGGAUUUUGGGAGCUUAAACAGACUUCUAAAAAUGUUUUAAAUUUAAACUUUGUAUUAAGUGUACAGAAAGUUUUAAGUAUACAAAAACCUAAGGAGGAUUGUAUAAUUAACCCCUAUACAUUCAUCACCUGGCUUCAACAAUUAUUAACAUGUGGCUCAUAUUGUUUUGUCUGUACUGCCUGCACCUCUCUAGAUUAUUUUAAAGUAAAUUCCAGGUAUCAUAUAAUUUUACCUGUAAAUAUAUGACUGUGUAUUACUAAGAAAUAAGGACUCUUAACACAUCUUCAGUACCAUUAUCAUAUCAGAAAAAUCACUUAAUAAUUCCUUAAUAUCUAAUAAGUGAUCACAGUUCCCCAGUUGCCUCAUCAAUGUCUUUUUUACUAUUGGAUUAUUCAAAUCAGCUUUCAAACAUGGUCCACACAUUAUAUUUGGUUGUUAUGUUUGUGGAUCUCUUUCAGUCUAUAACAGCCUCCUUCCCCUCCUUUUCUUGCUGUUUAUUUACCCAAUUUGUCCUGUAGAAUUUUUCACAAUCUUUAUUUGGCAGACUCAUGGUAUCCUUUAAAAUGUUCCUCUGUUCUGUUUGUGGUGAACUUGUUGCUAGAUCUCGGCAUGCUGAGAUUCAGGUUUUACUUUUUUUCCUCCCAAGCUAUGUCAUGGGUGGUGUGGUAUGCUUCUUGCCUGUUGCGUUACACAGGGAGGCACAUAGCAAUGUCUGUCUUGCCAUUUCUCUUUUUGUAUGUUCAAGUUGAUCAUGGAGUUCAGUGUUAUUAGCUUGAUCCAGCCAUUAUGAAACGUAUUCUUUCCUUCUUUCUUUCUUUUUUGAGAUGGAGUUUCACUCUGUCACCAGGCAGGGGUGCAGUGGUGCUGUCUCGGCUCACUGCAACCUCUGCCUCCCGGGUUCAAGCGAUUCUCCUGCCUCAGCCUCCUGAGUAGCUGGGACUACAGGCGUGCGCCACCACGCUUGGCUAAUUUUUGUAUUUUUAGUAGAGACGGGGUUUCGUCAUGUUGACCAGGAUGGUUUUGAUCUCUUGACCUUGUGAUCCUCCCACCUCAGCCUCCCAAAGUGCUGGCAUUACAGGCAUGAGCCACUGUGCCUGGCCAAAAUGUAUUCUUUCAAUGAACUAUUACAUUUUGGGUCUUCUAAUUUUAUUCUCAAAGGGUACUUUGCUGUCAAAUGUUAUUGCCUUCUGAUACGUUCUCUGUAUGCAGCGAGAAUGAUCUUUUAAAUAUAAAAUGGAUUACAUACUACCUACCUUGCUUAAAACUCAAUAGUGUUCCAUUGCUUGUAAACUGACAUCUAAACUUCCUACCAUAGUCUAUAGGAAUCUGCAUAACCUGGGGUUUAUCUGGCUUUCUAAACCUCAUUUUAUGCCAUUCUGUCCUUUGAGAGGCAAUGUGGCAUUAUUGUUAAUAGCUUGGGCUCUUGUACUAGACUGGGGUUGGGGUGUGAUCUUGGGUAGGUCACUAAACUGCUCUGUCCCUCCAUUUUUUCAUAUCAAAAAUUGAUGUUCUAAUAGUAUUUACCAAUAGGAUUGUGAUGAUUAACACAUAUCAAUAGCAAUAUUGUGAUGAUUAAAUAAUGAAUAUCAAUCACCUACAACAAUGCCUGUAUAACAUAACAAAUACCUAAUGUUAGCUGUUGUGGUUGCUGCUGGCGUUGAUGCUUUGUUUUUUAUGUCUGUGUUCAGCUACACUGUACUUUGCAGUUUCUGGACCUGACAAGCUCUUGCCAGCCUCAAGAUCUUUGCACAUUGUUCUCAUUGUCUCUCUUGCAACAUGACAAACCAUCCCAAAAUUUAGUGGCUUAAAAAAACAAUUGUUUAGCUUACAAAUGUGCAAUUUUGGCAGAGUUUGUGAGAGAGAGCUCAUCUCUGUUCCAUAUGGCAUUGGCUGGGGUGGCUUAACUGAGGGCUGUGGGGUUUACUUUUAAACGGGUCACUCAUGUGGUUGGCAAGAUAGUCUUUACUCUUGGCCAGGAAGUCAACUAGGGUGGAGGUCUUGAUUCCUCUUGAUUCCUCUCCACAGGCUGCUUGUCCUUACAGCAUGGUGGCUGGGUUCUAAGAGUGAGUAUCCUAAGAGAAGCAGGCAGAAGCUGAAUGGCCUAAUACAAUGUAGACUCAAGAAGUACACAGUGUUACUUUUGCCUCAUUAUUUUGGUUCAGGCAGUCACAAAGGCCCACUCAGGCUUAAGGGGAGAGAGCACAUGGACUCUACCUCUUGAUAGGGAAAUAACAAGGUGUUCUAAAAGAGGGACAGGAGAUACUGUUGCAGCCAUCUUUGGGGAAUGUACUUUGCCAUACACAUGCUGUUGCCUGAACCUGAAACACUAUCAUCUGUCAGAUUCCCACUCUUUAGCAAACUAACCAACUUCAAUUAGGUCCCUCUUUUUCCAUUGCCUUUGUUUGCUCUCUUUCUCAUAGCUCUUCAUUUUCCUUGGUAACACUUACCACAGUUUGUAAUUUUUUAAAGUCCAUGGGUGUUAUGACCUGUCAUGUACUAAGUACCUAGCAUUGGACCUGUUGAAAUGUUAAAAUGUGUUGUUACUUACAAAUCUAAAUAUCAUGUAUUACAUUCGCACUAAGGAAAGCGUGUUCCAAACUUUGUGGAAAAAAAUGGAACAAAUACACAGAAACACCAGGAGUCAGUCCUUUAACUCCUUAAAGUUCAUGCCUUACUCUUUAGCUUAGGGUGAGGAUGCGAUGAAGAAAAACAUAUGUAAAAAUGUUGGGGUGGGAGGAGAACUCAGUUGGAAUAGCUGAAUUUCUACUUACCCUCCCCAUACUUUAAAAACCCAAACCCACAAAUCUGUUUUCUAUUCCUCUAUCACCCCGUGCGUGGCAAGAAGCUUCUAGCUGGUCCUCAAAAUAUUUUUGUUGAGAAGAAAGCAUGAUAACUAAGAAAUGUUUAGUACUCUCAGGGAAUAGCCAAAUAUAUUUACUUUACUCAGGGAAAGCAAAACACACCUUCACUCAGUACUAGUGUUUUUGUUUUGUUUUGUUUUGUUUUGUUUUGUUUUGUUUUACUUUUGACACAGUUCUAACAAGAUUGGUUAUCAGGUUUCUCAGCCCCCAGCAGACUGGGCAGGGAAAAGAGAAUAGACUUUCGGAAGUGAGGUAUAGAUAAUAGCAAAGAGAACAGCUGUUGUUGGCCUCAGGAAAUACUUUUUCAAAACCUUGAGCAAUGAUGACAUUGUAGCCUGGGAAUUGUAGUAAUGUGGGGUAGAAGGUCCCAUACAUUUUAAAAGAAUUUCAUUCACUUAACAGAUAUUGUGUGCAGUCUUGCUGAUUGUUGGAGACACAAGGUGAACAAAAUGCACAUGGCCCCUGCCUUCAUGGAGAUUUCAUUCUGGGGAUGGGGCAGACCUUAUGAUUGAUAUUUGCGAGGUAUAUCUUUUUUCAUCCUCUUUUAACCUAUAGGUGUCUUUAUAUUUAAAAUGAUUUUUAAGGUGGUCUUCAAAAUGGUUUUCUUAUAAGCAUCAUAUAGGUUGUUGCUUUAUAUACAAUCUGACAAUUUCUGCCUUUUAUUUUUUAUUUUUUUAAUUUAUUUUCUAAGAGACAGGGUCUUGCAGUGUUGCCUAGGCUGGACUUCAAAUUCCUGAGCUCACCUCAGCCUCCCAGGUAGCUGGGACUACAGGCAAAUGCCAUGGCACCUAGCUAAUCUCUGCCUUUUAAUUGUGGGUGUUUAGAUCAUGUACAUUUAAUAUUAUUGAUAUGAUUGGGUUUAAGUCUACCAUCUUAUGUAUGUUCUGUUUGUUCCAUCUGUUCUUUAUUCCUCUCCUUCUUUUCUCUUUUGCAUUACUUUAGAUUGAGUGUUUUUUUAUGAUUUAUUUCAUCUCUUUUGUUAGCUUACUAACUAUACCUUUUCUUUUUAAAUGAUUCUUUAGGGUUUAUAGUAUACAUCUUUAACUUAUCACAGUCUACCUUUAGGUGAUCCAUUUUACUACUUCAUAUAUAAUAAGAACCUUACAAUAAUACAGUUUUAUCUCCCUGCCUUUGUUAUUGUUAUAUAUUUAAUCCUAAUGUUAUAAACCCCACUUUUUUUUUUUUUUUUUUUGAGAUGGAGUCUUGCUCUGUUGCCCAGGCUGGAGUGCAGUGGCAUGAUCUUGGCUCAUUGCAACCUCUGCCUCCCAGGUUCAAGCAACUCUCCUGCUUCAGCCUCCCGAGAUUACAUGCACCCACCACCACACCCGGCUAAUUUUGUAUUUUUAGUAGAGACGGGGUUUUACCAUGUUGGCCACUGUGGUCUUGAACUCCUGACCUCAGGUGAUCCACCCACCUCGGCCUCCCAAAGUGCUGGGAUUACCGGCGUGAGCCACCACACCCGGCCACUUUUUUUUUUUUUUUUUACUUAAACGGUCAAUUAUCUUUUAAAGAGACUUUUGCAAUUAAAAUAUAUAUGUAUUUACCUGCAUAUUUACCCCUUUUGGUGCUCUUCAUUCCUUUGAGUAGAUCCAGAUAUCUAUAUGGAAUCAUUUUCUUCUUCCUAAAACUUUUCUUUAACAUUUUCUCAUAGUCAGGUCCACUAAUGAUGGAUUCUUUCAGCUUUUGUAUGUCUGAGAAAAUCUUUAUUCCACUCUCCUGUUUUUAAGAGUUUUUUUUUUUUAAGGUAAAAUUCACAUAACAUAAACCAUUAACCAUUCAAAAGUGCAAUUCAGUGCAUUUAGUACAUUCACAGUGUUAUGUAACCAUCACCUCUAUGUAGUUCUAAGACAUUUUCAUUACCCUAAAUUCACUUGGGUAAAUUCUGAAAGAUGAAAGAUGUUUUUUGCUGGGUAGAAAAUCGUUAGGUUGACAAGUUUUUUUUCUUUCUAUACUUUAUAGAUAUUCUGUCUUCUUCUGGUUUGCAUUGUUUCCAAUGAGAAGUCAACUGCCAUUCUUAUUUUCAAUUGUAUGUAAUAUGCUCCAUAACCCAAGACUGUGCUUAAGGUUUUAUCAUUGGCUUUAAGUAAUUUAAUUAUGAUGUCCCUUUGCCCUUGGCAUAGUUUUCUUAAUUUUUUUUUUGCGCUUGUGGUUUGUUGAACUUCUCAGAUCUAUGGCUUUAUAGUAGUAUCAGAUUUGGACAUUUUUUCAAGCAAAAUUCUUAAAAUAAUUUAUUUUGGAAACAGCUCUUGACCUGUUGUCGAGGCUGGAGUGCAGUGGCAUGAUCACGGCUCACUGCAGCCUCAACCUCCUGGGCUCAAGCAGUUCUUCCACCUCGGCCUCUUGAGUAGCUGGGACCACAGGUGUGAGCCACCAUGUCCAGCUAUUUUUUUUUUUUUAAUAUUUUUUUAGAGACAGGGUCUUGCCAUGUUGCCCAGACUGGUCUUGAACUCCUGGCCUCAAGAUUCUCCCACCUGAGCUUCCAAAAGUUCUGGGAUUACAGGUAUGAGCUACCACCUGGCCCAAUUAUUUUUAAUCCUUCCCACUUUUGAGGACUUCAGUUGCAUGCAUAUUAGGUUGCUUGAAGUUAUCCCACAGUAAUCAAUCACAUUAGUACUAUAUUUUUUUUUCAGGGUUUUUUUCUGUGCUUCAUUUUGGAUAGUUUUGAUUUCUAUCUUAUCAAAUUAACUGGUUUCCUUUUUUUUCUGUAAUGCCUUAUCUGCUUUUUAUUUCAUCCAGACAUUUUCAUCUCUAGAAAAUUGAUUUGGGGCUUUUUAAUACGUUCAAGUGUAACUGCUUAUGUCUUCGUCUACCUUAUUGAACAUGUAGACUGUAGUUUUAAUAACUAUCUUAAUGUUCUUGUCUACCUGUUCUAUCAUCUAUGUCAUUUCUGGGUGUGUUUCUGUUUAUUGAAUUUCCUGCUCAUUAUGGGUUAUGUUUUACUUAUCCACUGAAUGUUAGAUAUUUAGGAUUUUAUCUUAUUGGGUGCUAUUUUUGUAUUCUAUUAUUUUUUAUUUUUUUGAGACAGGGUGUCACUCUUGUUGCCCAGGCUGGAGUGCAGUGGUGUACCAUGGCUCACUGCAGCCUCAACUUCCUGGACUCAAGUGGUCCUCCCACCUCAGCCUCCCAAGUAGCUGGGACUACAUGUACACACCACCAUGCCCAGCUAAUUUUUUGUAUUUUUAGGAGAGAUGGGGUUUCACCAUGUUGCCCAGGCUUGUCUUGAAUUCCUGGGCUCAAGUGAUCUGCCUGCCUUGGCCUCCCAAAAUGCUGGUAUUACAGGUGUGAGCCACCGUGCCCAGACUUAUAUUCUUUUAAAUAUUCUUGAGCUUUGUUCUGAGACUCAGUGAAGUUGAUUGGAAACAGUAUGAUCUUUUCAAAGCUUACUUUUAAGCUGUGUUGUGUGGGACCAGAGCAGCCUUUUACUGUACAGCUAAUUUUAGCUCAUUACUGAGGAGAUGCCUUUAUGGAAACUUUACCCAAUGUCCCAUGUGCUCUCCCUUCUGGCUGAAUGAACAUGAACUGUUUCUGGUUUUAUGUGAGUCCUGGGGAUUGUUCUACUUGCUCUUCCUAGUGGCUCUUCUCUGGACUUAGACUGUCUUGACAAAGGGAACAACCUAUCUUCAGCACUCGAGCUCAUGUCUUCCAAAUUGACCCAAACACAAAGAAGAACUGGGUACCCACCAGCAAGCAUGCAGUUACUGUGUCUUAUUUCUAUGACAGCACAAGAAAUGUGUAUAGGAUAAUCAGUUUAGAUGGCUCAAAGGCAAUAAUAAAUAGUACCAUCACCCCAAACAUGACAUUUACUAAAACAUCUCAGAAGUUUGGCCAGUGGGCUGAUAGCCGGGCAAACACCGUUUAUGGAUUGGGAUUCUCCUCUGAGCAUCAUCUUUCGAAAUUUGCAGAAAAGUUUCAGGAAUUUAAAGAAGCUGCUCGACUAGCAAAGGAAAAAUCACAAGAGAAGAUGGAACUUACCAGUACACCUUCACAGGAAUCCGCAGGCGGGGAUCUUCAGUCUCCUUUAACACCGGAAAGUAUCAACGGGACAGAUGAUGAAAGAACACCUGAUGUGACACAGAACUCAGAGCCAAGGGCUGAACCAACUCAGAAUGCAUUGCCAUUUUCACAUAGUUCAGCAAUCAGCAAACAUUGGGAGGCUGAACUGGCUACCCUCAAAGGAAAUAAUGCCAAACUCACUGCAGCCCUGCUGGAGUCCACUGCCAAUGUGAAACAAUGGAAACAGCAACUUGCUGCCUAUCAAGAGGAAGCAGAACGUCUGCACAAGCGGGUGACUGAACUUGAAUGUGUUAGUAGCCAAGCAAAUGCAGUACAUACUCAUAAGACAGAAUUAAAUCAGACAAUACAAGAACUGGAAGAGACACUGAAACUGAAGGAAGAGGAAAUAGAAAGGUUAAAACAAGAAAUUGAUAAUGCCAGAGAACUACAAGAACAGAGGGAUUCUUUGACUCAGAAACUACAGGAAGUAGAAAUUCGGAACAAAGACCUGGAGGGACAACUGUCUGACUUAGAGCAACGUCUGGAGAAAAGUCAGAAUGAACAAGAAGCUUUUCGCAAUAACCUGAAGACACUCUUAGAAAUUCUGGAUGGAAAGAUAUUUGAACUAACAGAAUUACGAGAUAACUUGGCCAAGCUACUAGAAUGCAGCUAAGGAAAGUGAAAUUUCAGUGCCAAUUAAUUAAAAGAUACACUGUCUCUCUUCAUAGGACUGUUUAGGCUCUGCAUCAAGAUUGCACAAAAAAAAAAAAAAAAAAAUUGAAUAUCACUCCUCCAGGAGGAGGAUCUUUUGAAAUUGGAAUUGUAUAUUUCACUGUAAAUUUUAGAAUCCAGCUUGUAGCUAGUUGGGGAAAAAAGAUGAAAAACUUGAACUACAAAUUACCUCCAUGUAUAUUAUUGGCCAUAGUUAACUAGAAAGUUAUAAAUAGACACUUAAUGCAAUCUUUUUUCCUGAUAUUAGCCAAUGGGAGAAUUAACAAUGUCUAGGUCACAUCCCCUUUUUGUGUUCAACACAGUGAAGAUUAUCUGCUUUUUAAAUUAAUUUAUUUACGAUAUCUAGAGCUGUGUUUUGUGCAAAAACUUAGUGAUGAAAGCCUGUCUUUUGUUGUAAUCUGAAUAAUUUCUCAGGAUAUUUUUGCACUGCUGAGAAGCAGUGCCAUUACCAAUUAAUUCUUGCCAGGAGUGAGAGAGAGCUGUAUCUUUAAUUGAAAUAUACUAUAACUGGGUGUAUAGAGUUCUUCCCUUUUUUGUGCUGGAAGAUAUUUCACUCUGGUGACUACUCUGGUACACUCUGGUGUUCUCUAAUCUUGUCUGUUGUAUAGUUUACUUUUCCAUAUUGAUUCCAUGUAUUUAUGAGAAGAUAUUGUCUCCCAUUUUAUUACACAUUUUAAAGCCAACUAACGAAGGCAGCUGAGUCCCUCAGAAAUUUUUCUUUUUAAGUUUCUAAUAAAUUUGACACACAGUACUGAAAUACAGCAGCCCGUCAUUGACAGGCUGGUCUAGCAAUGUUAAGUAUAUUUACAGAAUAUGCAGUUACAUUUAUUUAUAUAUUUUGCAAGAAAUCUUUUCUGAAUGAUCAAUGCAUUUCAAUUUACGAAUAAUAAUGGUUAUUGGGGAACUGUUUAUUAUAGAUAAUUUUAAGGUGUAUAGCUAUUUUAAAGGGGGUCCAUUUACAUCAAACAGCUGAUCAGAGGACUCUAUCUAAAUUGUGAUCGUGGCAGAUAGAGAUGGAGUCAUGUACUCUAUCUGGCUCUACACAUCAAUCACAUCUUGAUUCAAACCUCACAAGGCAAUAUUCUGAAUUGUUAACUAGGUAUUUCAAAACAGGAAUUAAAUUCAAUAGGCUCUUCUCAGUGAACAGGUUUUAAUGUUGUUUUGAUGUAAUUUUAAAAGACUUUUAGCAAACAUGCAUUUCUUUAUAUGAUAUAUUUCUUUUACGAAGCUAUUUUAAAAGUAAGCCAAGUGCUGUCUAGUCUGCUUAUAAAGUAGGAAUUGCAUCAGAGUACAUAUAUUCUUGCUGUACAAUGCCUGUGAUGUUGAGGAGGGUUCUUUUUUAAAGUGUAUGCUUGAGUAACUGACUCUAUGGAGUCUAUAAAUGCACUGACUUCUUGUUUGUACCCCAAAAUGAUCGAAUUGUUAAGUACAAAAUUAAGCUAAUUAACCAAUUUGUAACCAUUUUUUCACUCAUAAACAGCUACUCAAUACUAGACAAUUUUGUUUUUUAUGUAUGUGUAUGUACGUAAAUACAUACAUAUUAAUUUACAUUAGAGUGAAAAAUAAAUGGUUUGUUUCUGAAGUUAGUUUCUUAAGUGAGUUUUCAGGUGUCUCUGAAAAAUUUAUAACAAUCAUGUAUUAUAUGUGCUGUAACAUCAUGUACGUUACCUCCAUCUAUUUUAGGAUAUUUUCCUCACCUAUAUAUUAUAGGGAGAAUAAUUUAGAUACACAUGCUCAGAGCUGAGAUAUUUCUCUGAUAAAUCAGGUAACAAAAUGUAUUUGAUUGAUGGAAUUUUGAAGUAAAUGUGUUUUUAUCCAUCAGUUUCUGAGUAACAAAGAGCACCAAGUUUUAAUUUAAAUAGGAGAUUUAACACUAGGGAUCAGGGAGUUUAGUAUGAAGAGUUAAAAAAAUUUAAAAAACAGUGUAAGCUGUUGAAAUGGCAAGUGAAUUAUUUUAAUGAUGUAAUAAAAUAUUUUUAAAUUUUGACAUAGUGAUCAUUUAAUGAAAAAACUCACCAAAAUGUCUCCAUUUGAAUUGUAUUGAUAAUGUGGGACAUAUGUGUGAUUCAAUAUAUACAUAUACCCAUAUGUAUAUACAGAAAAUUAUUUUUAAUACUUUCCUACUGAUAAUGAAAUUUAAAAUUGGAAAUUUUGUGAGUGUUUUUCUUGUCCAAUAGAGCCUAAUUGUUUCCUUUUUUAGUGAUUUAACAAUCUCUUGAGGGCUGCACCUUUAAAUUCCCAGAUUGUCAAUAGACAUGUACAGUAUAUGGGAUAAGGUGGACACAAGUGCACAUAUAAAUAAAAUCUUCUUAAGACUUUUAACUAUUCAUUUACAGUAGGAGAGUAUGUAGAAAUCAUCAUCCACAAGUCAUAAUUAGGUUGUGUGCCUACUGUAGUUUUUUCCAUUUCUGUAUUAUAUAAACAUUUGCAUAUUAAAAUUUGAUUUUUCCCAGAGACAAGUAUUAUAUACUGUAUCUAUAUUUAAAUCAAACUGUGGUAAUAUAUUUCUCAGAAAAUAAUGUUGGGGACUAUAGCCUGAACAUGUGGACUUGAAGCGACAUGGAGGAGGAGGUUGAUCCCAUUGUGUAUAAGUUAAUAUGUGAUAACUAUUGAAUCUUGUACAAAAACAAAAAUUGAAAAAAAAAAAGAAAAGCAAAAAUACAGUUUUUAUUUUGAAAUACAUUUGUUCUCUGGAGAAUGUACUUUAUCUUUUUUUCCUCCAGUCUUUUACAGAUAUUUAAAAGCAUUUAAAUGAUGACAGCAUUUACUUAAAUCUUUCAGGUGCUACUGGAUUUUGCAUUAGUGUGUUAUGUUGUGAAAUCCUAACUUUGACAUAAAAGGUUUUAUAAGUAUUCCCCUGCCUGGAAAAUUAGUUUUUGUUCUCCUCUCUCUCUCUUUCUCUUUUCCACUUUCUUUCUGCAGACUAAAACAUGCUCACGAAGUUGCAUCUCUCCUUGUCUCUAUAGAAGAUCUCCAGCACCAUCAUAGAUUUGAUGUUCUGCUGUCAUUGAACUGUUGGGAAGCAGUUAGAGGAAAAGCUCACUUUUUUUUUCAGGUGGAAAUAAAAGGAACACUCAAAAUUAAGCCAACACCACCACUACCUUUAAAAACUAGUUUAUUUGCCCUGUUAAAAUUAAAUGUAUUCUUUAACAUGUGGGCUACAGUCUCCCAUGUUUUUAUUUAACUGAAGCAUAUACACUUCGGUCAUUUAUCUCCUUGUGGUCCUGAUUUUGUCAGUACUGGAAUGGGAGGCAGGUCGGGGAAAGUUUGUUUGAUGGCAGUGGAUUCUUAUUGUUGUUUUAACCAUUGCAUUU